AUAACAUCCUGUGCGCUGCUGAGCUGAGCUGGGGCGCAGCCGCCUGUCUGCACCGGCAGCACCAUGUCGCUCAUGGUCGUCAGCAUGGCGUGUGUUGGGUUGUUCUUGGUCCAGAGGGCCGGUCCACACAUGGGUGGUCAGGACAAACCCUUCCUGUCUGCCUGGCCCAGCGCUGUGGUGCCUCGAGGAGGACACGUGACUCUUCGGUGUCACUAUCAUCAUAGGUUUAACAAUUUCAUGCUAUACAAAGAAGACGGAAUCCACAUUCCCAUCUUCCAUGGCAGAAUAUUCCAGGAGAGCUUCAACAUGAGCCCUGUGACCACAGCACAUGCAGGGAACUACACAUGUCGGGGUUCACACCCACACUCCCCCACUGGGUGGUUGGCACCCAGCAACCCCGUGGUGAUCAUGGUCACAGGAAACCACAGAAAACCUUCCCUCCUGGCCCACCCAGGUCCCCUGGUGAAAUCAGGAGAGAGAGUCAUCCUGCAAUGUUGGUCAGAUAUCAUGUUUGAGCACUUCUUUCUGCACAAAGAGGGGAUCUCUAAGGACCCCUCACGCCUCGUUGGACAGAUCCAUGAUGGGGUCUCCAAGGCCAAUUUCUCCAUCGGUCCCAUGAUGCUUGCCCUUGCAGGGACCUACAGAUGCUACGGUUCUGUUACUCACACCUCCUAUCAGUUGUCAGCUCCCAGUGAUCCCCUGGACAUCGUGGUCACAGGUCCAUAUGAGAAACCUUCUCUCUCAGCCCAGCCGGGCCCCAAGGUUCAGGCAGGAGAGAGCGUGACCUUGUCCUGUAGCUCCCGGAGCUCCUAUGACAUGUACCAUCUAUCCAGGGAGGGGGGAGCCCAUGAACGUAGGCUCCCUGCAGUGCGCAAGGUCAACAGAACAUUCCAGGCAGAUUUCCCUCUGGGCCCUGCCACCCACGGAGGGACCUACAGAUGCUUUGGCUCUUUCCGUCACUCUCCCUACGAGUUGUCAGACCCGAGUGACCCACUGCUUGUUUCUGUCACAGGAAACCCUUCAAGUAGUUGGCCUUCACCCACAGAACCAAGCUCCAAAUCUGGUAACCCCAGACACCUGCAUGUUCUCAUUGGGACCUCAGUGGUCAUCAUCCUCUUCAUCCUCCUCCUCUUCUUUCUCCUUCAUCUCUGGUACUCCAACAAAAAAAAUGCUGCUGUAAUGGACCAAGAGCCUGCAGGGAACAGAACAGCCAACAGCGAGGACUCUGAUGAACAAGACCCUCAGGAGGUGACAUACGCACAGUUGGAUCACUGCGUUUUCACACAGAGAAAAAUCACUCGCCCUUCUCAGAGGCCCAAGACACCCCCUACAGAUACCAUCUUGUACACGGAACUUCCAAAUGCUAAGCCCAGAUCCAAAGUUGUCUCCUGCCCAUGAGCACCACAGUCAGGCCUUGAGGGCGUCUUCUAGGGAGACAACAGCCCUGUCUCAAAACCGAGUUGCCAGCUCCCAUGUACCAGCAGCUGGAAUCUGAAGGCCUGAGUCUUCAUCUUAGGGCAUCGCUCCUCCUCACGCCACAAAUCUGGUGCCUCUCUCUUGCUUACAAAUGUCUAGGUCCCCACUGCCUGCUGGAAAGAAAACACACUCCUUUGCUUAGCCCACAGUUCUCCAUUUCACUUGACCCCUGCCCACCUCUCCAACCUAACUGGCUUACUUCCUAGUCUACUUGAGGCUGCGAUCACACUGAGGAACUCACAAUUCCAAACAUACAAGAGGCUCCCUCUUGACGUGGCACUUACCCACGUGCUGUUCCACCUUCCCUCAUGCUGUUUCACCUUUCUUCGGACUAUUUUCCAGCCUUCUGUCAGCAGUGAAACUUAUAAAAUUUUUUGUGAUUUCAAUGUAGCUGUCUCCUCUUCAAAUAAACAUGUCUGCCCUCA